AGCCUGCGGAGCCAGCGGCCGUGACGCGACAACGAUUCGGCUGUGACGCGACAACGAUUCGGCUGUGACGCGAGCGCGGCCGCUCCCGAUGCGCUCGUGCCGCCCCCGCCGUGCUCCUCGGCAGCCGUUGCUCGGCCGGUUUUGGUAGGCCCGGGCCGCCGCCAGGCCUCCGCCUGAGCCCGCACCCGCCAUGGACAACUACGCAGAUCUUUCGGAUACCGAGCUGACCACCUUGCUGCGCCGGUACAACAUCCCGCACGGGCCUGUAGUAGGAUCAACUCGUAGGCUUUACGAGAAGAAGAUCUUCGAGUACGAGACCCAGAGGCGGCGGCUCUCGCCCCCCAGCUCGUCCGCCGCCUCCUCUUAUAGCUUCUCUGACUUGAAUUCGACUAGAGGGGAUGCAGAUAUGUAUGAUCUUCCCAAGAAAGAGGACGCUUUACUCUACCAGAGCAAGGGCUACAAUGACGACUACUAUGAAGAGAGCUACUUCACCACCAGGACUUAUGGGGAGCCCGAGUCUGCCGGCCCGUCCAGGGCUGUCCGCCAGUCAGUGACUUCAUUCCCAGAUGCUGACGCUUUCCAUCACCAGGUGCAUGAUGACGAUCUUUUGUCUUCUUCUGAAGAGGAGUGCAAGGAUAGGGAACGCCCCAUGUACGGCCGGGACAGUGCCUACCAGAGCAUCACGCACUACCGCCCUGUUUCAGCCUCCAGGAGCUCCCUGGACCUGUCCUAUUAUCCUACUUCCUCCUCCACCUCUUUUAUGUCCUCCUCAUCAUCUUCCUCUUCAUGGCUCACCCGCCGUGCCAUCCGGCCUGAAAACCGUGCUCCUGGGGCUGGGCUGGGCCAGGAUCGCCAGGUCCCGCUCUGGGGCCAGCUGCUGCUUUUCCUGGUCUUUGUGAUCGUCCUCUUCUUCAUUUACCACUUCAUGCAGGCUGAAGAAGGCAACCCCUUCUAGAGGGAGCCAUGAGGGUCUGGGCUUCAGAGCUAGGUCUUUGGGGAAGUCCUGGCUGACUGCCUUAGCAGUGGGGGUGGGGGUGGGGGCAGGGGCAGGGGCUUUAUGUGUUUUUGCUUGGGGGGCGCUGGGCCUAGCCCAGAGUAGUGCUUGCUCCCCCUGCCUUGUCCCACCAGGGAGGCAGCAGACUCAGGCCCUCCAUGGUCCUCUUUGUCAUUUUGUUGACAUGCAUUCCUCCUUUUGUCAUCUUGUUGGGGGGAGGGGAUUAACCAAAGGCCACCCUGACUUUGUUUUUGUGGACACACAAUAAAAGCCCCGUUUAUUUGUAA